GCCUCUCCGGAUUCUGUUAACGGUAGUGGUGGCUUGUUGGGAUCCGUUGAGUGAUGGGAGAGUGUGCUCUUUAACUUCGGAGAGAGAUGCGCUCUCGUGUAGCCGUCAGGGCCUGCCAUAAGGUCUGCAGGUGCCUGUUGUCUGGGUUUGGGGGUCGAGUAGAUGCGGGGCAGCCGGAGCUGUUGACGGAAAGGAGUAGCCCCAAAGGAGGGCAUGUGAAGUCGCACGCGGAGCUCGAGGGGAACGGCGAGCACCCAGAAGCCCCCGGGUCUGGAGAGGGAAGCGAGGCGCUGUUAGAGAUCUGUCAGAGAAGGCAUUUCCUAAGUGGAAGCAAGCAGCAGCUUAGCCGGGAUUCUCUUCUGAGUGGGUGCCACCCCGGCUUCGGACCCUUGGGCGUAGAGUUGCGGAAGAACCUGGCCGCAGAAUGGUGGACCUCGGUGGUGGUGUUCAGGGAGCAGGUAUUCCCGGUGGACGCCCUCCACCACAAACCAGGCCCUUUGCUACCCGGGGACAGUGCCUUCAGGUUAGUUUCUGCAGAAACUCUACGCGAAAUCUUGCAAGACAAAGAGCUGAGUAAGGAACAGCUAGUAGCAUUUCUUGAGAACGUAUUAAAAACUUCUGGGAAACUACGGGAGAACCUUCUUCACGGUGCCUUGGAACACUAUGUUAAUUGCCUGGAUCUGGUAAACAAGAGGCUACCUUAUGGCCUUGCUCAGAUUGGAGUGUGUUUUCAUCCUGUUUUUGACACUAAGCAGAUACGAAAUGGUGUUAAAAGUAUUGGUGAGAAGACUGAAGCUUCGUUAGUAUGGUUUACUCCUCCGAGAACUUCAAACCAGUGGCUUGAUUUCUGGUUACGUCAUCGACUCCAGUGGUGGAGAAAGUUUGCCAUGAGUCCAUCUAACUUCAGCAGCAGUGACUGUCAGGAUGAAGAAGGCCGGAAAGGAAACAAACUUUACUACAAUUUUCCCUGGGGAAAGGAGUUAAUAGAAACCCUGUGGAACCUAGGAGAUCACGAACUUUUACACAUGUAUCCUGGCAAUGUGUCUAAAUUACAUAUGCAGAGACACUCACCUACAUAACUACAAUCCAGUCAUCAAAAUCAGGAAAUUAACAGUAAUCCACUAUUGCCACAGAGCCCUACAAAUUGAACUGAUUAUCUCAAUAAUGGCAUUUAUAGGUCCAAGAUCUUGUCUUUCAUGUAGUUGUCAUAUGCCUUUACACUCCUUCAAAUGAACAAUUCCUCUUGUCUUGCGUGACCUUGACAUUUUUGAAGAGUACAGUCUAGUUAAUCUGUAGAAUAUGCCUUGGCUGGGAUCUGUCUGCUGUUUCCACGUGAUUUAUGUAUUUUUGUCGGGAGUACUACAGAAGUGGUAGUACUGAGAAGCUCUCUUCUCAGUGUGUCAUAUGAGGAGUGUUACUGGUGAUGUUAACUUUUAUCAUUUAGUUAAGAUGGUUUCUACUAGAUUUCUCCAGUGUAAAGCUAAUAAAUAGUUUGUAUUUAUUAAUUAACGGCCAGGCGCAGUGGCUCACGCCUGUAAUCCCAGCACUUUGUGAGGCCGAAGUGGGAGGAUCAUGAGGUCAAGAGAUUGAGACCAUCCUGGCCAAUGUGGUGAAACCCCAUCUCUACUAAAAAUACAAAAAUUAGCUGGAUGUGGUGGCUUGCCCUUAUAGUCUCAGCUACUUGGGAGGCUGAGGCAGGAGAAUCGCUUGAACCCGGGAGGUGGAGGUUGCGAUGAGCCAAGAUCGUGCCACUGCACUGCAGCCUGGCGACAGAACGAGACUCUGUCUCAAAAAAAAAAAACAAAAAAAUUAACUAGUAAUUAAUAAGUGUUGUGGGCAGAUACUUUAAGAUGAUGCAGACAAUUUCUUUGUCACCAAAUUUUGCCUUACUGGUUGCAGCAUCCAUUGAUGAUUCUUGCCCAGAUCAGUUACUAAUGUGAGGUUUGCCAAAUGGUGAUUUUUUUUUUUCUUUAUUUGAGACAGGAUCUCACUCUAUCACUCAGGCUGAAACACAGUGGUAUGGUGAUAGCUCACUGCAACCUCAAACUCUUGAGCUCAAGCAAUCCUGCCUCAGCCUCCCAAGUAGCUAGGACUACAAGCAUGUAUCACCAUGCCCGACUGAUGGUUUAAUAUUUGUAGAGACGGGGUCUAGCUUUGUUGCCCGGGCUGGUCUCGAACUCCUGGGAUGAAACAAUCCCCCUGCCUCAGCCUCCCAAAAUGCUUGGAUUAUAAGAAUGAGUCACCAUGUUUGGCCAUGUCACCAAAUUUUGCCUUACUGGUUGCAGCAUCCCUUGAUGAUUCUUGCUCAAAUCAGUUACUACGAUGAGGUUUGCCAAUGGUGUUUUUUUCCCCUUCCCUUUUUUUUUUUUUUAAAAAAAAACAAAUUCCAUCAUUCCUUCUAGAUUUACUGGUCAGCAAUAUACUGUAGAGCUUUUCCUUCUCCUCCAUUUUUUUUUUAAAUUGGUAUUUCACAGAUUACUUUCUCAGGGGGUUACAGUGUGUUACUGUCAUUAUUUAUUUUGAUGGUCAAAUUGUCCUAGACUUGGCCAGUGUCCUUUUGACAUAUUUCCAUCAUUGUCUUGACGAGCACUUCCUUACCUUUUGUAGCAAUAUAUUGUUCCAGGAUCAUCAGUGAGCCAAGACUGUGCUGCUGCACUCCAGCCUGUGCAACAGGAUGAGACCAUGUCUCAAAAAAAAAAAAAAAGAAAAAGAAAAAAUAUAUAGCAAAAACAUAGGAGUUUAUAUAUAAUGAGUAGAAAGUAGAUUAAUUUUUAUUUUUUUAUUUUUUGAGACAGCAUCUCACUCUGUUGCCCAGGCUGGAGUGCAGUGUCGCGAUUCCCAGGUUCAAGCAGUUCUUCUGCCUCAGCCUCCUGAGUAGCUAGGACUAUAGGUGUGCGCCACCACGCCCGGUUAAUUUUUGUAUUUUUAGUAGAGACAGGGUUUCACCAUAUUGACCAGGCUGGAAUUUUUAAAUAUGAAUAACUAAUGAAAAACUAGAAGGCUUAUUAACUGGUGAACAUUUUCCUUUAACUCCACCACCAUCACACUUCAUUUUGGGGUACUCAGCUCUCAAAUGAAACUUAUUGGUUAUUAUCAUAGUUAACGAACAGCUCAACCUUGUGACUAGGGAUUUAAAGAUGAUUUUUGUAUUGUGGCUAUUAGUGUCUUAUUUUGUUCUUUUUUUUCUUUUGUAUGAAGAAUGGGGUCUCGCUAUGUUGCCCAGUCUGGUCUUGAAUUCCUGGGCUCAAGCUGUUCUCCUGCCUCUGCCUUUCUGAGUGCUAAGAUUACAGGUGUGAACUACCAUGCCCAGAUUAUUUUGUUCUUUUAUUGGUAUCAUUUUCACUAAUGAAGAGUUUUCCUAUUGCAGAAAUUUUUCUCUUCCAUGACAUUGUUCCUUUUCUGUUUCCAGAGUUCACAAAAUUAUUUAUCAUUAGUUGAACAUGUUAUAAAAUAUUAAGUAGAAUUUCUGUCAUUUAGUAUGCUUUCUUGAAAUGUUUCUGAGGCCAUUUCUUUCUUUUUUUAAAAUUAUUUAAUAGAGAUGGGGUCUCGCUGUGUUGCUCAGGCUGGUCUUGAACUCCUGGGCUCAAGCAAUCCUCCUGCCUUAGCCUCCCAAAGUGCUGGGAUUAUAGGCGUAAACCACUGCACCCAGCCUCUUAGGCCAUUUUGUAUCUGUUUUUAGUUGAUUUUAUGGUUAAUGUCCAAAUAUAUUUUUUAGAGAACAGUGAAGCAGACCAAUAAAGGCUGAAGAACAGUUAGGAUAGAAAAGAAUUUAUUCUGGAUAGUGUGAGAAAUCAGAUAUUGUUGGAAGAGUUGCCACCAGAUAUCCUGACAUUGUUGGAUAUCCAAUUUUCAAAAAAUUAGAAAACAAUAAACAAUCUUUUUUGUUUGUUUUAAAUAGGGAUGGGAUCUUGCCAUGUUGCCCAGGCUAGUCUCAAACUCCUGGGCUCAAGUGAUCCUCCUGCCCUGGCCUCCCAAAGUGCUAGGAUUACAGGAGUGAGUCACUGUGCCCAGCCUAAAGCAUUCUUCAUAAAGAUUCAGAUUUAGAUUUUGUUUGAUUCAAAGCGCACCACAGAAUCUUUCAGUACUUGAGUUUGUCUUUUUUUUUUUUUUUUUUUUUUUGAGAUGGUGUCUCACUCUGUCACCCAGGCUGGAGUAUAGUGGCACAAUGUCUGCUCACUGCAGCCUCCACCUCCUGGGUUCAAGUGAUUCUCAUGCCUCAGCCUGCUGAGUAGCUGGGAUUACAAGCAUGCACCACCAUGCCCAGCUAAUUUUUGUCUUUUUAGUAGAGGUGGGGUUUUACCAUGUUGGCCAGGCUGGUCUCGAACUCCUGAACUCAAGUGAUUCGUCCACCAUGGCCUCCCGAUGUGCUGGGAUUACAGGCAUGAGCCACUGCUCCCAGCCCAGUUUAUCUUAUUAACUAUCAGUUCGACGAUAACUGUGUGAAAUACAACUGGUAGAAUAGAGUCCCAGGUAUCAGAAAGUUUACUGCCUUUGAGGGCAAAUUCUUGUGAAUCUUUAAAGUAUCAUAUGCAAUUCAAAUAGGUUUAAAAUGUCAGUACAUAUAUGUAUUAAUGAAGACUGUGGUUGAUCAUGAAUAAUUAACAGAAGCUGAGGAUUUAAA